AGUUCCUGUUAGGCCCCGGCCGGGGGAGUAGGUUGAAGUCUCCUAAGAUGCCCGGUGGGCUGGGGCACCGGGAGCUGUGAAGGGAACGUGAGGGGGCGGCGUAGUGGAGACCCACGGCAGGCCUGAAGAAGAGCGGCGGCCGAGCCCGCCUUCCCUGCACCAUGCUCAUAGAGGAUGUGGAUGCCCUCAAGUCCUGGCUGGCCAAGUUACUGGAGCCGAUAUGUGAUGCUGAUCCUUCAGCCUUAGCCAACUAUGUUGUAGCACUGGUCAAGAAGGACAAACCUGAGAAAGAAUUAAAAGCCUUUUGUGCUGAUCAACUUGAUGUCUUUUUACAAAAAGAAACUUCAGGUUUUGUGGACAAACUAUUUGAAAGUCUCUAUACUAAGAACUACCUUCCACUUUUGGAACCAGUAAAGCCUGAGCCAAAACCACUAGUCCAAGAAAAAGAAGAAAUUAAAGAAGAGGUAUUUCAGGAGCCAGCAGAGGAAGAACGAGAUGGCAGAAAAAAGAAAUAUCCUAGUCCCCAGAAGACUCGUUCAGAAUCUAGUGAACGAAGGACACGUGAGAAAAAAAGAGAAGACGGGAAAUGGAGAGACUAUGACCGGUACUAUGAGCGGAAUGAAUUGUACCGUGAGAAGUAUGACUGGAGAAGAGGCAGGAGUAAGAGUCGGAGUAAGAGUCGAGGCCUGAGUCGCAGUAGAAGCCGAAGUAGGGGGCGCAGCAAAGACCGGGAUCCAAAUAGGAAUGUUGAGCACAGGGAAAGAUCGAAGUUUAAGAGUGAAAGGAAUGACCUGGAGAGUUCCUAUGUGCCUGUGUCUGCACCACCUCCAAACUCUUCUGAGCAGUAUUCCUCUGGGGCACAGUCUAUUCCCAGCACUGUUACUGUGAUCGCACCUGCUCACCACUCUGAAAACACAACUGAGAGUUGGUCUAAUUACUAUAACAAUCAUAGCUCUUCCAAUUCUUUUGGUCGAAACCUACCACCAAAGAGGCGAUGCAGAGAUUAUGAUGAAAGAGGAUUUUGUGUACUUGGUGACCUUUGUCAGUUUGAUCAUGGAAAUGAUCCCCUAGUUGUUGAUGAAGUUGCUCUGCCAAGUAUGAUUCCUUUCCCACCCCCUCCUCCUGGGCUUCCUCCUCCACCACCUCCUGGAAUGUUAAUGCCUCCAAUGCCAGGUCCAGGCCCAGGCCCGGGCCCAGGUCCAGGCCCAGGCCCGGGCCCAGGUCCAGGUCCUGGCCAUAGUAUGAGACUUCCUGUUCCCCAAGGACAUGGUCAGCCUCCACCAUCCGUUGUGCUUCCCAUACCAAGACCACCUAUAACACAAUCAAGCUUGAUAAACAGCCGUGACCAGCCUGGGACAAGUGCAGUGCCCAAUCUUGCAUCAGUGGGAACAAGACUACCUCCUCCUUUACCCCAGAACCUCCUUUACACAGUAUCAGAACAUACAUAUGAACCAGAUGGUUACAACCCAGAAGCUCCUAGUAUUACUAGUUCUGGUAGAUCUCAGUACAGACAGUUCUUUUCAAGAACUCAGACACAGCGUCCCAAUCUGAUUGGCCUAACAUCUGGAGAUAUGGAUGUAAAUCCAAGAGCUGCUAACAUUGUGAUCCAGACUGAACCACCAGUUCCUGUUUCGAUUAAUAGCAACAUAACCAGAGUAGUUCUUGAACCAGAUAGUCGAAAAAGAGCUAUGAGUGGUUUGGAAGGGCCACUCACAAAGAAACCUUGGCUGGGAAAGCAAGGAAAUAACAAUCAAAAUAAACCAGGGUUCUUACGAAAGAAUCAGUAUACAAACACCAAAUUAGAAGUCAAGAAAAUCCCUCAGGAAUUGAACAACAUUACCAAGCUCAAUGAACACUUCAGCAAAUUUGGAACUAUUGUUAAUAUCCAGGUUGCUUUUAAGGGUGACCCAGAAGCAGCCCUAAUCCAAUAUCUUACCAAUGAGGAGGCCAGGAAAGCCAUUUCUAGCACAGAAGCAGUUCUAAACAACCGAUUCAUUCGAGUCUUGUGGCAUAGGGAAAAUAAUGAGCAACCGACACUACAGUCCUCAGCACAGCUGCUCCUGCAACAACAGCAAACACUUAGUCACCUCUCACAGCAGCACCAUCACCUGCCACAGCAUCUACAUCAGCAGCAGGUGCUAGUGGCCCAGUCUGCUCCUUCAACAGUGCACGGAGGUAUCCAGAAGAUGAUGAGCAAACCACAGACAUCAGGUGCAUAUGUUCUUAACAAAGUUCCUGUUAAACAUCGUCUUGGACAUGCAGGUGGUAACCAGAGUGAUGCAUCACAUUUGUUGAAUCAGUCUGGUGGUGCUGGAGAAGAUUGCCAGAUAUUUUCAACUCCAGGCCAUCCAAAAAUGAUUUACAGCUCCUCAAACUUAAAGACACCUUCAAAGCUCUGUUCAGGGUCUAAAUCUCAUGAUGUUCAAGAAGUGCUUAAAAAAAAACAGGAAGCAAUGAAGUUACAACAAGAUAUGAGGAAAAAAAGACAGGAAGUGUUAGAAAAGCAAAUAGAAUGCCAAAAGAUGUUAAUAUCCAAGUUAGAAAAAAACAAAAACAUGAAACCAGAAGAAAGAGCAAAUAUAAUGAAGACUUUGAAAGAGCUUGGAGAGAAGAUCUCACAAUUAAAAGAUGAAUUAAAAACAUCUUCUGCAGUCUCCACACCAUCUAAAGUGAAGACAAAAACGGAGGCCCAGAAGGAGUUAUUAGAUACUGAACUGGACCUCCACAAGAGGCUGUCCUCAGGAGAAGACACCACAGAAUUACGGAAAAAACUCAGUCAGUUACAGGUUGAGGCUGCACGGUUAGGUAUUUUACCUGUGGGUCGAGGAAAGACCAUGUCCUCUCAAGGUCGAGGAAGAGGCCGAGGGCGUGGAGGAAGAGGAAGGGGCUCACUAAAUCACAUGGUGGUGGACCAUCGUCCCAAAGCACUAACAGUUGGAGGAUUCAUUGAGGAAGAAAAAGAAGACUUGCUUCAGCAUUUCUCAGAGCGCGAAGAUGAUGGCCAUGAACUCCAAGCAGCCUUUCGGCAUGCACCCGGUGCUGCAAGAACCCAAAUUCUCCAGUCUGCACUCUGGCUCCGAGGCCAUGCGCCGAGUCUGUCUCCCAGCCCCGCAGCUGCAGGGUAAUAUAUUUGGAAGCUUUGAUGAGAGCCUGCUGGCACGCGCCGAAGCUCUGGCGGCGGUGGAUAUCGUCUCCCACGGCAAGAACCAUCCGUUCAAGCCCGACGCCACCUACCAUACCAUGAGCAGCGUGCCCUGCACGUCCACUUCGUCCACCGUGCCCAUCUCCCACCCAGCUGCGCUCACCUCACACCCUCACCACGCCGUGCACCAGGGCCUCGAAGGCGACCUGCUGGAGCACAUCUCGCCCACGCUGAGUGUGAGCGGCCUGGGCGCUCCGGAACACUCGGUGAUGCCCGCACAGAUCCAUCCACACCACCUGGGCGCCAUGGGCCACCUGCACCAGGCCAUGGGCAUGAGUCACCCGCACACCGUGGCCCCUCAUAGCGCCAUGCCUGCAUGCCUCAGCGACGUGGAGUCAGACCCGCGCGAGCUGGAAGCCUUCGCCGAGCGCUUCAAGCAGCGGCGCAUCAAGCUGGGGGUGACCCAGGCGGACGUGGGCGCGGCUCUGGCUAAUCUCAAGAUCCCCGGCGUGGGCUCGCUGAGCCAAAGCACCAUCUGCAGGUUCGAGUCUCUCACUCUCUCGCACAACAACAUGAUCGCUCUCAAGCCGGUGCUCCAGGCCUGGUUGGAGGAGGCCGAGGCCGCCUACCGAGAGAAGAACAGCAAGCCAGAGCUCUUCAACGGCAGCGAACGGAAGCGCAAACGCACGUCCAUCGCGGCGCCGGAGAAGCGUUCACUCGAGGCCUAUUUCGCUAUCCAGCCACGUCCUUCAUCUGAGAAGAUCGCGGCCAUCGCUGAGAAACUGGACCUUAAAAAGAACGUGGUGAGAGUCUGGUUCUGCAACCAGAGACAGAAACAGAAACGAAUGAAGUAUUCGGCUGUCCACUGAUUGCGGCAGGGCGCAGCGUCGGGAGCCGGGAGAGCCUAGUGCUCAUCCCUCCCGGGUUCGGGGGAUGGUUAUCGGGAACUCCAAGGCGUUUCCUAGGCAGGUUAGGCUCUCUCCUCCGAAGCCACAGACUUUCCCCCUUUGUCCCGCCUGGUUGCCUCCGGCCUUCUCUCUCUUUCCUUUCUAUUCCCACCAAAAAAAUUUUGGCGCUGGGAAAAUAUUGCAGAAGGGCGGGCCUGAGUGUACUUGUGCUGUCCGUGGUGCUGAAAUUUGCCCUCGCGCAGGGGCCGCACGACUUCAGAGCAGGAGCCCCAAAGCAGAGGACAGUCAAUUGGCCCAACCGCCCGAAGCUAGGGUGAAAAUGCCACUUUGCUAAGCGCGAUUAGGCAAAGGGUGAAGGGAUAAAAAGGAAGUGAUCAAUAAUAACACAAAGUCUAGGAUAUCUAAGGGGGACACAAACAUGCACUGGAGAUUUAUUAGAGUAUAUAAAAUACAUGUAUGUUUCCAAAGGAUAGCCUUAUACUCCCUUCCUUGCCUAAAUUCUAUUCACCUUAUCCUUUGGUUUGGCGUAAAUUCUCAUAAGGUAGCAUGAAGAUUAGGUUCAGGGAAAGUAUGCAGGGAGUUGCGGGCUCCAAGUUGCCAUUUUUUCGUGGUAAGUAGGGCUCCAAAACAGGUGGGCCCAGUCUGGCGACUGAAAAUUCUGGGAUCGCUUGGCUGUUUGUAAUCAGCUGCCAGCACCAGCUCUGGCCAUCUUUCACUACCUACUGGUGUUUGAGGGGUAAUUACUGCUUGCUGGAGAGCGGGAGUUUGUAGUAUUCAUAACCGUUGAGGACUCUCUGACCCCAGCUCGCUGCUCUUGCCAGAUUGCCAGCUCAGCGUGCAGUCGGCUGCUGGAAAACGACUGUAACUUCUCUGCAUUAUAUGCAAGUCCUUUCAACACGUCUAACCUCCUUGCACUUUUGUUAUUACUGUUGUUGUUAACAUCGUUCAUUACUAUUAUUUAUUUAAUUCUGCUUCUUUCCAUUCCCUUUAUGUGGGUGUCUUUCGGUGGAAGUUCACUUAUAGUUUUGUGAGGGAAGAGGAGUGGGACCAUGGGCCUGAACCCUUCUCACCCUGCCCCUCUAGCCCAAAUUUUAUUUUAUUUUUUCGUUGUUUCAUGUAGUUUGUGUGUUGCUGUGUGACCUUUGGUUUCAUUCUCUGAAUAGAUACAAAUAAAAUAUUAAGUUUUCUUUUCCCUUUACCCCUUGAAUUAACUUCUAAAAUAAAUGCUUUAUUUUUCAACCCGAA